GCGUAACCCUUGCGGCGCCGGCCGAACCGCGCCAGAGCUGGCGCGGGGAAAGGGAGAUAGGUGUCUCCAGCUGCUGUGGCUGUUUGGGGCGGGUCGGCUUCAUCCGCGUCUCAGGAGCAAGUAGAGAAUUAGCGGGCGGCAGCAAUGCUCCGCAAGGUGAGAAGCUGGACAGAAAUCUGGCGGUGGGCUACCCUUUUGUUCCUCUUUUACCACCUGGGUUACGUUUGUGGGCAGAUCCGCUACCCGGUCCCAGAGGAGUCACAGGAAGGGACUUUUGUAGGGAAUGUCGCUCAAGAUUUCCUGCUGGAUACGGACAGUCUGUCAGCUCGCAGGCUGCAGGUCGCUGGAGAGGUGAACCAAAGACACUUCCGUGUGGAUUUGGACAGCGGAGCCCUGCUCAUCAAGAACCCAAUCGACCGAGAGGCACUGUGUGGGCUCAGUGCCAGCUGCAUCGUGCCCCUGGAGUUUGUCACCGAAGGUCCUUUGGAAAUGUACCGAGCAGAGGUAGAGAUCGUAGAUGUGAAUGAUCACGCCCCCCGUUUUCCGCGGCAGCAGCUGGACUUGGAAAUUGGGGAGGCAGCUCCUCCAGGACAGCGUUUCCCGUUGGAAAAGGCUCAGGAUGCAGAUGUGGGGAGCAAUUCGAUUAGCAGCUAUAGGCUGAGCUCCAAUGAACACUUUGCACUGGAUGUGAAGAAGCGCAGCGACGGCAGCCUGGUCCCAGAGCUGCUCCUGGAGAAGCCUUUGGAUCGAGAGAAGCAAUCGGACUACCGCCUGGUGCUGACUGCUGUCGAUGGAGGGAACCCGCCGAGAUCUGGCACCGCAGAGCUCCGGGUAUCCGUGCUGGACGUAAACGACAACGCCCCAGCCUUCCAGCAAUCCAGCUACAGGAUUAGUGUGUUGGAGAGCGCACCAGCGGGCAUGGUGCUCAUCCAGCUCAAUGCCUCAGACCCGGACCUGGGUCCCAGUGGUAACGUCACCUUUUAUUUCAGUGGUCAUACCCCUGAUCGUGUAAGAAACCUCUUUAGCCUGCACCCCACUACUGGAAAGCUUACUCUUUUGGGGCCCCUAGACUUUGAGAGUGAGAAUUACUAUGAAUUUGAUGUGCGGGCUCGCGAUGGGGGUUCUCCAGCCAUGGAGCAACAUUGCAGCCUUCGAGUGGAUCUGCUGGACGUAAAUGACAAUGCCCCUUACAUCACAGUGACCUCAGAGCUUGGAACCCUCCCCGAGAGUGCAGAACCUGGCACUGUGGUGGCACUUAUCAGUGUGCAGGAUCCAGACUCAGGGUCAAACGGAGAUGUGAGCCUCCGCAUUCCUGACCACUUGCCAUUUGCCCUCAAGUCUGCCUUCAGGAACCAGUUCUCCCUGGUGACUGCUGGACCCUUGGAUCGAGAGGCCAAAUCUAGCUAUGACAUCAUGGUCACUGCUUCUGAUGCUGGGAACCCUCCUCUCAGUACCCACAGAACUAUUUUCCUCAAUAUUUCAGAUGUGAAUGAUAAUCCACCCUCUUUCUUUCAGAGGUCACAUGAGGUGUUUGUUCCUGAGAACAAUCGCCCAGGGGACCUGCUUUGCUCCCUUGCAGCCUCUGACCCAGACUCUGGCUUGAAUGCGCUUAUCUCCUACUCACUCCUGGAGCCCAGGAAUCGAGAUGUAUCAGCUUCCUCUUUCAUCUCUCUGAACCCCCAGACAGGAGCUGUUCAUGCUACUCGAUCCUUUGACUAUGAGCAAACCCAGACACUGCAGUUUGAGGUGCAGGCCCGGGAUCGGGGCAACCCACCCCUUAGCAGCACUGUAACAGUUCGUCUAUUUGUGCUGGACCUCAAUGACAAUGCUCCAGCUGUGCUCCGUCCUCGGGCCCGGCCUGGUUCCUUAUGUCCCCAAGCACUGCCUCCAUCAGUUGGUGCUGGCCACCUAAUCACAAAGGUGACUGCUGUGGACUUGGAUUCAGGUUACAAUGCUUGGGUUUCCUAUCAGCUCCUGGAGGCCCCAGAUCCCAGCCUGUUUGCAGUCUCUCGAUAUGCUGGGGAGGUGCGGACGGCUGUUCCUAUCCCAGCUGACCUCCCACCACAGAAGCUGGUCAUUGUGGUAAAGGAUAGUGGUAGUCCACCACUCUCUACCUCUGUUACUCUCUUAGUGUCCUUAGAGGAAGACACUCAUCCAGUUGUCCCAGAUCUUCGAGAAUCUUCAGCUCCAAGGGAAGGAGAAUCUCGUCUAACCCUCUACUUGGCUGUGUCCCUAGUGGCAAUUUGCUUUGUCUCCUUUGGCUCAUUCGUGGCACUACUCUCUAAGUGUCUUCGUGGGGCAGCCUGUGGAGUCACAUGCUUUCCUGCUGGCACCUGUGCCUGUCUCACCAGAUCUCGAAGGAGGGAGGGGCUUCCCCCUUCCAAUGGGAUCCUCCGAAUCCAGCUAGGGUCAGAUGACCCUAUCAAGUUUGUUGAUGUGGGAGGCCACUCUCAUGGCUGUACACCCUUGGCUUCUGCACCCACUCGGAGUGAUAGCUUCAUGAUGGUGAAGUCACCCAGUGCACCUAUGGCAGGGGAGCCUGUUCGCCCAAGCUGCCCACCCUCUGAUCUUCUCUAUGGGCUAGAGCAAGCCCCGCCCAACACGGACUGGCGUUUCUCUCAGGCCCAGAGACCCGGCACCAGCGGCUCCCAAAAUGGCGAUGACACCGGCACCUGGCCCAACAACCAGUUUGACACAGAGAUGCUGCAAGCCAUGAUCUUGGCGUCCGCCAGUGAAGCUGCUGAUGGGAGCUCCACCCUGGGAGGGGGUGCCGGCACCAUGGGAUUGAGCGCCCGCUACGGACCCCAGUUCACCCUGCAGCACGUGCCCGACUACCGCCAGAAUGUCUACAUCCCAGGCAGCAAUGCCACACUGACCAACGCAGCUGGCAAGCGGGAUGGCAAGGCCCCAGCAGGUGGCAAUGGCAACAAGAAGAAGUCGGGCAAGAAGGAGAAGAAGUAACAUGGAGGCCAGGCCAAGAGCCACAGGGCGGCCUCUCCCCAACCAGCCCAGCUUCUCCUUACCUGCACCCAGGCCUCAGAGUUUCAGGGCUAACCCCCAGAAUACUGGUAGGGGCCAAGGCCAUGCUCCCCUUGGGAAACAGAAACAAGUGCCCAGUCAGCACCUACCCCUUCCCCCCCAGGGGGUUGAAUAUGCAAAAGCAGUUCCGCUGGGAACCCCCAUCCAAUCAACUGCUGUACCCAUGGGGGUAGUGGGGUUACUGUAGACACCAAGAACCAUUUGCCACACCCCGUUUAGUUACAGCUGAACUCCUCCAUCUUCCAAAUCAAUCAGGCCCAUCCAUCCCAUGCCUCCCUCCUCCCCACCCCACUCCAACAGUUCCUCUUUCCCGAGUAAGGUGGUUGGGGUGUUGAAGUACCAAGUAACCUACAAGCCUCCUAGUUCUGAAAAGUUGGAAGGGCAUCAUGACCUCUUGGCCUCUCCUUUGAUUCUCAAUCUUCCCCCAAAGCAUGGUUUGGUGCCAGCCCCUUCACCUCCUUCCAGAGCCCAAGAUCAAUGCUCAAGUUUUGGAGGACAUGAUCACCAUCCCCAUGGUACUGAUGCUUGCUGGAUUUAGGGAGGGCAUUUUGCUACCAAGCCUCUUCCCAACGCCCUGGGGACCAGUCUUCUGUUUUGUUUUUCAUUGUUUGACGUUUCCACUGCAUGCCUUGACUUCCCCCACCUCCUCCUCAAACAAGAGACUCCACUGCAUGUUCCAAGACAGUAUGGGGUGGUAAGAUAAGGAAGGGAAGUGUGUGGAUGUGGAUGGUGGGGGCAUGGACAAAGCUUGACACAUCAAGUUAUCAAGGCCUUGGAGGAGGCUCUGUAUGUCCUCAGGGGACUGACAACAUCCUCCAGAUUCCAGCCAUAAACCAAUAACUAGGCUGGACCCUUCCCACUACAUAAUAGGGCUCAGCCCAGGCAGCCAGCUUUGGGCUGAGCUAACAGGACCAAUGGAUUAAACUGGCAUUUCAGUCCAAGGAAGCUCGAAGCAGGUUUAGGACCAGGUCCCCUUGAGAGGUCAGAGGGGCCUCUGUGGGUGCUGGGUACUCCAGAGGUGCCACUGGUGGAAGGGUCAGCGGAGCCCCAGCAGGAAGGGUGGGCCAGCCAGGCCAUUCUUAGUCCCUGGGUUGGGGAGGCAGGGAGCUAGGGCAGGGACCAAAUGAACAGAAAGUCUCAGCCCAGGAUGGGGCUUCUUCAACAGGGCCCCUGCCCUCCUGAAGCCUCAGUCCUUCACCUUGCCAGGUGCCGUUUCUCUUCCGUGAAGGCCACUGCCCAGGUCCCCAGUGCGCCCCCUAGUGGCCAUAGCCUGGUUAAAGUUCCCCAGUGCCUCCUUGUGCAUAGACCUUCUUCUCCCACCCCCUUCUGCCCCUGGGUCCCCGGCCAUCCAGCGGGGCUGCCAGAGAACCCCAGACCUGCCCUUACAGUAGUGUAGCGCCCCCUCCCUCUUUCGGCUGGUGUAGAAUAGCCAGUAGUGUAGUGCGGUGUGCUUUUACGUGAUGGCGGGUGGGCAGCGGGCGGCGGGCUCCGCGCAGCCGUCUGUCCUUGAUCUGCCCGCGGCGGCCCGUGUUGUGUUUUGUGCUGUGUCCACGCGCUAAGGCGACCCCCUCCCCCGUACUGACUUCUCCUAUAAGCGCUUCUCUUCGCAUAGUCACGUAGCUCCCACCCCACCCUCUUCCUGUGUCUCACGCAAGUUUUAUACUCUAAUAUUUAUAUGGCUUUUUUUCUUCGACAAAAAAAUAAUAAAACGUUUCUUCUGAAAA